GCUUUACCUGUCCAGGUAGCCUCUGUUUUCAUUUCAGUCUUAAUGAAAACUUUCUAACUUAUAUCUCAAGUUUCUUUUCAAAGCAGUGUAAGUAGUAUUUAAAAUGUUAUACUUCAAGAAAGAAAGACUUUAACGAUAUUCAGCGUUGGUCUUGUAACGCUGAAGGUAAUUCAUUUUUUAAUCGGUCUGCACAGCAAGAACUGAAACGAAUGGGGAUUGAACUGCUUUGCCUGUUCUUUCUAUUUCUAGGAAGGAAUGAUCACGUACAAGGUGGCUGUGCCCUGGGAGGUGCAGAAACCUGUGAAGACUGCCUGCUUAUUGGACCUCAGUGUGCCUGGUGUGCUCAGGAGAAUUUUACUCAUCCAUCUGGAGUUGGCGAAAGGUGUGAUACCCCAGCAAACCUUUUAGCUAAAGGAUGUCAAUUAAACUUCAUCGAAAACCCUGUCUCCCAAGUAGAAAUACUUAAAAAUAAGCCUCUCAGUGUAGGCAGACAGAAAAAUAGUUCUGACAUUGUUCAGAUUGCGCCUCAAAGCUUGAUCCUUAAGUUGAGACCAGGUGGUGCGCAGACUCUGCAGGUGCAUGUCCGCCAGACUGAGGACUACCCGGUGGAUUUGUAUUACCUCAUGGACCUCUCCGCCUCCAUGGAUGACGACCUCAACACAAUAAAGGAGCUGGGCUCCCGGCUUUCCAAAGAGAUGUCUAAAUUAACCAGCAACUUUAGACUGGGCUUCGGAUCUUUUGUGGAAAAACCUGUAUCCCCUUUUGUGAAAACAACACCAGAAGAAAUUGCCAACCCUUGCAGUAGUAUUCCAUACUUCUGUUUACCUACAUUUGGAUUCAAGCACAUUUUGCCAUUGACAAAUGAUGCUGAAAGAUUCAAUGAAAUUGUGAAGAAUCAGAAAAUUUCUGCUAAUAUUGACACACCCGAAGGUGGAUUUGAUGCAAUUAUGCAAGCUGCUGUGUGUAAGGAAAAAAUUGGCUGGCGGAAUGACUCCCUCCACCUCCUGGUCUUUGUGAGUGAUGCUGAUUCUCAUUUUGGAAUGGACAGCAAACUAGCAGGCAUCGUCAUUCCUAAUGACGGGCUCUGUCACUUGGACAGCAAGAAUGAAUACUCCAUGUCAACUGUCUUGGAAUAUCCAACAAUUGGACAACUCAUUGAUAAACUGGUACAAAACAACGUGUUAUUGAUCUUCGCUGUAACCCAAGAACAAGUUCAUUUAUAUGAGAAUUACGCAAAACUUAUUCCUGGAGCUACAGUAGGUCUACUUCAGAAGGACUCCGGAAACAUUCUCCAGCUGAUCAUCUCAGCUUAUGAAGAACUGCGGUCUGAGGUGGAACUGGAAGUAUUAGGAGACACUGAAGGACUCAACUUGUCAUUUACAGCCAUCUGUAACAACGGUACCCUCUUCCAACACCAAAAGAAAUGCUCUCACAUGAAAGUGGGAGACACAGCUUCCUUCAGCGUGACUGUGAAUAUCCCACACUGCGAGAGAAGAAGCAGGCACAUUAUCAUAAAGCCUGUGGGGCUGGGGGAUGCCCUGGAAUUACUUGUCAGCCCAGAAUGCAACUGCGACUGUCAGAAAGAAGUGGAAGUGAACAGCUCCAAAUGUCACCACGGGAACGGCUCUUUCCAGUGUGGGGUGUGUGCCUGCCACCCUGGCCACAUGGGGCCUCGCUGUGAGUGUGGCGAGGACAUGCUGAGCACAGAUUCCUGCAAGGAGGCCCCAGAUCAUCCCUCCUGCAGCGGAAGGGGUGACUGCUACUGUGGGCAGUGUAUCUGCCACUUGUCUCCCUAUGGAAACAUUUAUGGGCCUUAUUGCCAGUGUGACAAUUUCUCCUGCGUGAGACACAAAGGGCUGCUCUGCGGAGGUAACGGCGACUGUGACUGUGGUGAAUGUGUGUGCAGGAGCGGCUGGACUGGCGAGUACUGCAACUGCACCACCAGCACGGACUCCUGCGUCUCUGAAGAUGGAGUGCUCUGCAGCGGGCGCGGGGACUGUGUUUGUGGCAAGUGUGUUUGCACAAACCCUGGAGCCUCAGGACCAACCUGUGAACGAUGUCCUACCUGUGGUGACCCCUGUAACUCUAAACGGAGCUGCAUUGAGUGCCACCUGUCAGCAGCUGGCCAAGCCCGAGAAGAAUGUGUGGACAAGUGCAAACUAGCUGGUGCGACCAUCAGUGAAGAAGAAGAUUUCUCAAAGGAUGGUUCUGUUUCCUGCUCUCUGCAAGGAGAAAAUGAAUGUCUUAUUACAUUCCUAAUAACUACAGAUAAUGAGGGGAAAACCAUCAUUCACAGCAUCAAUGAAAAAGAUUGUCCGAAGCCUCCAAACAUUCCCAUGAUCAUGUUAGGGGUUUCCCUGGCUAUUCUUCUCAUCGGGGUUGUCCUACUGUGCAUCUGGAAGCUACUGGUGUCAUUUCAUGAUCGUAAAGAAGUUGCCAAAUUUGAAGCAGAACGAUCAAAAGCCAAGUGGCAAACGGGAACCAAUCCACUCUACAGAGGAUCCACAAGUACUUUUAAAAAUGUAACUUAUAAACACAGGGAAAAACAAAAGGUAGACCUUUCCACAGAUUGCUAGAACUACUUUAUGCAUGAAAAAAGUCUGUUUCACUGAUAUGAAAUGUUAAUGCACUAUUUAAUUUUUUUCUCUUUGUUGCUUCAAAAUGAGGUUGGUUUAAGAUAAUAAUAGGACAUCUGCAGAUAAGUCAUCCUCUACAUGAAGGUGACAGACUGUUGGCAGUUUCAAAAUAAUCAAGAAGAGAAAUAUCCUUAGCAAAGAGAUGACUUUGGGGAUCAUUUGAGGAAUACUAACUCUGUUGCAUUAAUGCUUCAAAAAAUCAUCAAAUGAUUCAUGGGGGCCUGAUUUGCAUUUGAAAAAUGUUUGAAAUUAGAGUCUCAUUUGUUUCAGGAAUGCAGCUACCUGAGUUUUUUGUCUCGGCAAAGUCACAAAGCCCAUAUACUCACAUUGUGUGUCUAUACUUGCCAAUUAAUUCUAAACUUGUAGGAAAUAUGCCCUCUCUUAAAGGAGAAUUUUUUUUAAAUCUCUGAGAAAUGAGAUUCUGAGUUUAUUUCAGCUAAAAGGUUGCAAUUCUUCUGAAGAUAUCUCAAAUAUAAGGUUGAAAGUUAAGUGUUAAUAAUUUUUGUGAAUUUAUACACACCUAAACGUUAAGUACACAAAUAUUUUAUUUGUUUUACAAAUAAGGAAUAAGUAAUUUAUAAAUUAAGAAGUUACCUAUAAAAAUAAAAAGAUAACAACCCUAUCAUAUAGCUUAUUUUUAAAUUACCUGAAAAACGAUAUUCUACACUGUUUCCUUUUUGACUCUGAGUUUUCAAACUGUUACUUCUCCCAUAUUUCUCAAUCCAUUUCACUCAGUUGCACAGUCUUUUAAACCCUGUAAUUGUCAUACCAAAGUUUCUUUUUAAAAAAAAAUUACUUUAAAUGCUUAGUUUAUUCAAAGAGCGAUCCAAUAAUAUAAAAGGAACAUGUGUUAAACACAAUAAAAUUUUAAAUGGCUCUAAAUCAAGCACAUCAAGAGUAUACAAGUCUUAAAGGCUUUUUAAUACAUACUCUUUUCCCAUCUAUGUAACCCAACUUGCACAUUUCAGCUGCAUGUGGUGAAUAUGCAUCAUAUAUUUACUUUAAGAGGUAAGAUUUUACUUGCAAAAUACAUGUGCAAAUUAGGGAUCCAUCAGUUGAUGGAAGAGAUGGACUCUAGAAUAUUAUUUCUUGUGGUUAUUACUCCUUUACAAAGCACUUUCGUCUCACUUGAUCCUCAUAAGGAAACUAAGGCUCAGAAUGAGUAGAGCUGGGUUCAGAAUCUAGCUCUUCUAACUCCAAGCCAUCUCCUCUUUCCACUGCAGGAAACUGCCUCUUUUGUCAGUGAAAUAAUAGAAAGAUUGUGUUAGUUAAGUGAUAACUGUCAUUUGUUUGAAAAUGUUCGAGACUGAACAAAUAGCAUUUAAACUGCUGGCAUAUAGAUGAGAUAUUGUACUUUUGUGCAAUGUUUAUUACCUUUGAUUAAAUUGUAAUGUGAAGCUUUUACUAGGUGAAUAGUUCAUUAUGUAGUGGAGGCUUCGUGGUUGUCCAUUGAAUUGUCACAGCAAAAUCUAUAAGUUUCUUCAAUUCUACAAGAUAGAUCCAUAUACCUUUGAUCACUUGGAGACUCUUUUUUUGCUGGUUUCUAGAUAACUCAGGUAAAUCAGACCUUUACAGAGUACAGGGCUAGGUGAAAGAAUUACUGAAAAAUCACCUUGAAAAUCCGAAGGGCUGAUAUACCCUUUAUGUUCCUGACUGAUGCGCAGAACCUGGGGGAAAUCUACAGCAAUAUACAGGUUGCAAUGCUGAUAACACAACAGCAAUCCUCUCCUCUACGUGGACUUACUGUUGUUUUUUUAAUUAUUAUUGGAAUGGGAUUUUAGAAAAUAGAAGUUACCUUUGUGUGUGUUUUAGGGAAGGUAGAGAAGAAUCUGCUCUUUCUCUGAAUACUGUUUUGACCCCAGGCAGGACCUUGGAAAGGCCAAAACAUUAACAGUAGUACUUCUGUUCACUGAAGAGUUAUGUUACAUGAAGAUAAAAUGGUUUUGUCGUGUUUAUUAUUGUAUUUUGUGUUGAUAUAAAUAAACAUGGUAAUUUAAACAAUGAA